AUGUAUAAGGCCUGAACUGUUAUACUUCUUUCCCUGUGAUCAGGUUCCAAGAAGGUUCUUCUGUUGUAUGUGGGCAUGUGUCUUUUGUAUAGUGUAUCAUUUUUCCUUUUCUCUUUACAUUUAGAUCAGACCAGCAUUAACCAGGCGAAUGAUUACUUGUACUUCCUUAACUGAUAGUUUACGUUUUGCAUUUAUUAUUAAUUUUUUUGAUUGUUAAGCCAAAGUUUGCUGCUCAGUAUACAUUCUGUUUAUUAUAUUCUAGGACAUAAGCAUUAAUUUUAAAACCGUCACAGCUUUGGUAAGGAUAUUGUGGAUUAGUACCAGGAUUGGUAGAUUUCUUCUGUUAUACUAGAAUUUCAGUGUAAUGCUGAUAGAUCAAAGUCAGAAUGCCUGUUGGAUACUCUGUUCAAUACUUGCACGACGGGAUCUUUCAUACUCCAAACCUCAGCAUCUGGCAGUAUACCCAGGUAAUAAGCCUGCACAUGUACUCACUGAAUCUAAAAUAAAAGUUGAAAAAAACAAACCAAAACAACAACAACUACAAAAAGUCAGAAUGCGUAACAAUUGAAAAAAAAAAAAAUUCGGUUUUAUUUUGUGCACAUAACAUCCAUUGCAUUUAGGAAAUAAUCUGUAUUUAUUUUUUAUUUAUUGUUAAACGUAUUUAUUAUUUUUAUUAUUAUUUAGAAAAGAAUCUGUUGGAUUGCUCCUCUGACAGAUUAGCUCCUUUCCCCUCCUGUUUCUGGUUCUUGUCCAUUUACAGUAUGUCAGUUCUACAUGAUUAUAUCUAUCUUUGGGUAGAUACAUUUCUGUGCUUUCCCCCUGAAUAUUGUGUCACAAAGAGUUUUCCAAUUUGGCAUUUAAUUUCCUAGUCAUUAUUUUUAAAUCUCUAAGAAUCUUAAACAGUUAAUCAUCUGAUUUUAAUUGUGAGAAGAAAACUUUUUUCUCCCACUGGUGUGUCACUCUCCUUUUCUUCUUAAAGUUGACCAUUCUGGUUUGGAGAUCAGCAGUUAUAAAAUUAUAGAUACGUAAUACCUCCCUCUUGCUUUUUAAUUCUUAAAUACUAUUUGAUGUCAUAUAUAAGGACAUCACAUUCAUAUACUGAACUGAAUAUUUUUGUUUAUUUAACAAAUAUAUAUUGUGUGCCUUCUAUAUCACCCAGCUAACUUAAGCAUUAUGUAAUGUAUGCAAAAUAGGAGAGUUUAUUAGAGACAAAUUAAAAAUAUUACUAUUAAUUAUCACCAUAGUUAUUACACUUAAUAAUAUACACUAUACAGUUCAUGACUGUUUUUUAUUAAGUGCCAGGCCCUAGCUCUAAGACAUUGGGAUGAUUCUAAGAUAGUUCAUAUGGUAAUUCAUUUAAUCUGCUCAGAAAUUAUGAGAUGGAGGUGAUAUCCAUAUUCUACAAACGAGGAAGCUGAAGCACUACGUAAGUUGUUCAGGGUCACGCAGCUAGUACGAGAAAGUGCUGGGAGGAAAUCUAAGAAGCUGUGGACCUGUCAUCAUCCUAGUUAUGAUUUAGUGUCAGGUCAGGCAUCCUCUUGAGUGCUGAAAAAAAUCUUUGCUUCUUUGGGAUUGACAGUCUUUUUUGCUGGCACCUGAGAUGGGCCUUGCUAAAGGACAUCUGUUUGUCUUCAAUAUCAUUGCCACGUUCUGCAGUUCCGUUAAGUGACCCUGUGUUGAGCAGUUUCUGUGGGCAAGGUACUGUUGCUGGAGUGGUCACUAGGAGAUACAGAAAUGAACAAGACCAUCCUGCCCUCAGCUUACAGUUUAAUCAGGAAGAAAGAUUAAACUGUAAGCUGAAAAUGUACACAAGAAAUGUACACAAGAAAAUGCACAAAAGAAAAUGCAGUACACAAGAAAAUGCAGUACAUACUGAGUGUGUGCACAAGAAAAUGCAGUACAUACUGAGUGUGUUGUAGAAGCUCAAAAAGAUUAUAGAAGCACAGAUACAUAUUUUAAUUCCAUGCCAUGGAGUCAGAGUAGAGAGCAUUUUAAUUGUUCCUUGAUGAAGUUAAUAGAAAGGCAAAGGGAAUUGACUAGCUUUCAUUAGGGAAAACUCUUUAGUAUGACAGUAGGAGACUGUUACUUGGAACUUGUCCAAAGAGAGAAAAAAGGAGAUGGGAAAUCUAAGAGCUAUAUUGGAACAAAUGGAUGAGAGAAGGGAUGCUGAUUUGGGACAUGACACCCAUACUGAAGCUGUCAGUAUCAGUACCUCCUCUGUUGGUCUACUACAUGUAUGAUCUGUUGAAAACCUCGUGAGAAGGGAAAUGUUUAUAGGCUAGAUGCUGUGCAGCUUCCAUCACCAUCUUGAAAGUAAUCCCUCCUUAUUAUCUCCCUGGUUCAUUCAUUUUACCUUUUGCAGUUGGUAAGAAUGGAAGCAUCUUCUCAAAAGAUGGUGCAAAUCUCUCUUUAGGCUUAUAAAAUAAUUUCAAUUGCCUAUAUUAAAAAGUUACCAGAAAGAAUUAGGAAGUCAGGAGCUUUUGAAAACUGUAUGUUUUUUCUCCCUCAGUCCAAAAAUAACCCACAGUUUUGGUUACAUUUCUUUUUUAUGUGUGUGCUGGUUAUCUUAUUUUAGUUUUCUGUUAGGAGAGCUUGAGGAUUUUAAUAGCAUUAAUCUUUUGCAAUGUAAAUUUUAUUCUAAUAAACAGUGAAGCAAUCUGUUAGCCUCUGUAGGGGCUAUAAAAGAACAUGAGUUGUGGCUACUGCUCUGCCCUCAGGAAGCUUAAGUUGUAUUUGAGAAGAUGAAAUUUUAAGAAAACCUCCGGAGGUACAAAUAGGUAAUGUGUUUUUAUCACGGUAGCAGCUUUUUUCUGUGUUGCCUUCUUGUUUUCCUGUGUUCAGCUAUAUUAAACUAUCAUUCACACUGCAGUUUUUAGCCCCUUCCCCAGCUGUGCACUACUCUGCCUCAAUUUAGGUGUAUCCUAGACAGUGAAGCUCUUCUUGAAGUCACGUACCUGGCUAACACUUUGUGUUCAUUGUAUCUUUUGUGAUGUUCUCUGUAGCACUUAAUUGUUUGCUUGUUUUGGCUAUUCAGAUUCUUUUUUGGUUCCAUAUGAAUUUUAGAAUGAUUUUUUCUAAUUCUGUGAAAAAUGGUGUUGGUAGUUUGAUAGGAAUAGCACCGAAUCUGUAGAUUGCUUUCAGCAGUAUGGCCAUUUUAACGAUCCUGAUUCUUCCAAUCCAUGAGCAUGGAAUGUUUUUCCAUUUGUUUGUAUCAUCUGUGAUUUCUUUUAGCAGUGUACAACACUUAAUUUUACUUUCUAGUAUGCUUGUCUUUCUCCCUCAUUUAGACUGUAAACUCCUUGAAGACAGAGCCUUGGACAUAGAGUUUACUCAGAUACCUUUGGGACUGGUAAGAACUUUGGAGAACAACAACAGGUGUUGGGGGACAGUGAUAAGUUUAAUAUUGGUGACUGCAUUUGAAGUACAGCAAGAUACUCAGAUAGAAAUGUCUGUUAACAGAACAUGGCCUGGCACUUGAUUAAGGUGGUAGAUGUAGGCCAUAAUAUGGUAUGAGUUGCCAAGAGGCCUGUGGAUAGAUCCCUGGGUAAUACCCUCAUUUAAGAUGUGGUAAAGAUUUUAAAAGGGGGUAAAUGUGAGCAGAGGAGGAUGGGUUAGAGACCUGUGAGAAUAAGUAAGUGAUACAAUGGACAGGAGGGAACAGUACUGUCAAGUGACACAGAAUUAAGAGGAGGAUGAGGACUGAUAAAAAGCCUGAGAUCAUUAAUAGAUGAUGGCUAAUAGAAGCAUUAAUAGAAGAUGGCUCUUCAUAGAGAGCCAUCUUAGUAGUGUGUGGACAGAAGAAUGGAUUCAGUUUGUCAGGGUCAAGGUGAGAGUGGGCCAUUAGGAGGAAGCAUUGUGAAUAGAUCUUUUUAAAAAGUGGGAUAAAAGGAGGGGGAGAAAAAGAAUAGCCUGAUGGGUUAUCAAAAUCCAGGAGAGACAUGUUUUUUGUUUUUUUUGUUUUUGUUUGUUUGUUUUUUGUGGCAGGGAGGUGGGUGGAGAAAAAUGGUCUUUUAUGUAGUAGAAUGUAUCUGAAUAUUGGCUAGUCUGAGGAAACCAAGAGAAAGGGGAUGGAAGUGGUGGUAGCUUGCAGUGGCAAUCAAGGAAGCAAGGUCUUGGAGCAGACUUGAGGACCCUGGAAAGAGCUGGAGUAAUUUAAGAAGGUCUUGGAAUUGAAAGAGGAACAUGACAGGAAGUUAGAGAUAUGUCCGUGGAUCAUAUAUGACUGAGAAAAAAUUCUGAUGGAACUAAGAACUCAGUUUUUAAACUUUUACCAACAUUGCUCAGCCAGAUGGUAUGUCUAUUCAGGGGUAGCUAAUUAACCAGAUGGGUGGUAGGAGGAUAAAGAGCAAGUGAGACAUAAGAGCAAAACUGGAGUCGCUGACCAUUGAGAAGUAAGCAUUUUUAGGGAGGCAAGUGUUGAUCAGAAAGGAUCUUGACUACCUUUGAACUUGAAGGUCAGAAUGUUUACACAAGACUCAGUAGAAGUGAAGAGAAAUAAAGUGAGAUAAGUUGUUCACUGGAGAGCAAAUUUUGAAAAUAGAACAAUUCCAAGGGAUGAUAAGUUUACCUUGUGGCCCUCCGCUUGAAUAGCAGGUAGAGAAUACAGAUCAAAGUCUUAGAAUGAAGGUCAAGAGUGUGUGAAACCAGAGAGUUUGAAGGAUCACCAACAUGUUGUGAUGGAGUGGGCUACAGUUCAACACAUCCCUGUUGCCCAUAUUCUUUGCACUUUGAUGUGUAUAUCUCAUGAUUGAUAUGGAGAAACUAGUCAUGGGCCAAAGGUCAAGAUACUUCUCUGGGAAAUGUUGCUGCUGAUGCUGCUUUACAAAGUCAUACAAUGAGUGUUUGGUUUAAGAAAGAUUUUCAUACUUAAAAGAUUUUCAUCUUGGAAAUACAUCAAGUGAAAAUUAAAUUCUUUUGGGAAACAUUUUCCUUCUGAUAUAUUAUACUUGUAAUGGGCGACAUGGCAAACAACUCAGUUGCUUACAGUGGUGUGAAAAACUCUUUGAAGGAAGCUAAUCAUGAUGGAGACUUUGGAAUUACGCUCGCAGAGCUGCGGGCUCUCAUGGAGCUCAGGUCCACAGAUGCAUUACGAAAAAUACAGGAAAGCUAUGGAGAUGUCUAUGGAAUUUGCACCAAAUUGAAAACAUCUCCCAAUGAAGGUUUAAGUGGAAACCCUGCAGAUUUAGAAAGAAGAGAAGCAGUGUUUGGAAAGAAUUUUAUACCUCCUAAAAAGCCAAAAACCUUUCUUCAAUUAGUAUGGGAAGCAUUACAAGAUGUCACUUUAAUUAUAUUAGAAAUUGCAGCCAUAGUAUCAUUGGGCCUUUCUUUUUAUCAGCCUCCAGAAGGGGAUAAUGCACUUUGUGGAGAAGUUUCUGUUGGGGAGGAAGAAGGUGAAGGUGAAACUGGUUGGAUUGAAGGAGCUGCAAUCCUCUUGUCUGUAGUGUGUGUGGUGUUAGUAACAGCUUUCAAUGACUGGAGUAAGGAAAAACAGUUUAGAGGUUUGCAGAGCCGAAUUGAACAAGAACAGAAGUUCACUGUCAUCAGGGGUGGUCAGGUCAUUCAGAUACCUGUAGCUGACAUUACUGUUGGAGAUAUUGCUCAAGUGAAAUAUGGUGAUCUUCUUCCAGCUGACGGCAUACUUAUUCAAGGCAACGAUCUUAAAAUUGAUGAAAGCUCAUUGACUGGUGAAUCAGAUCAUGUUAAAAAGUCUUUAGAUAAGGAUCCCUUACUUCUAUCAGGUACUCAUGUAAUGGAAGGCUCUGGAAGAAUGGUAGUUACAGCUGUAGGUGUAAAUUCUCAAACUGGAAUUAUCUUUACCUUACUUGGAGCUGGAGGUGAAGAGGAAGAGAAGAAAGAUGAGAAGAAAAAGGAAAAGAAAAAUAAGAAACAAGAUGGAGCUAUUGAGAAUCGCAACAAAGCAAAAGCCCAGGAUGGUGCAGCCAUGGAAAUGCAGCCAUUGAAGAGUGAAGAAGGUGGAGAUGGUGAUGAAAAAGAUAAAAAGAAAGCAAAUUUGCCAAAAAAGGAAAAAUCUGUUUUACAAGGGAAACUUACAAAACUGGCUGUUCAGAUUGGCAAAGCAGGUCUGUUGAUGUCUGCCAUCACAGUUAUCAUUCUAGUAUUAUAUUUUGUCAUUGACACCUUCUGGGUUCAGAAAAGACCAUGGCUUGCUGAGUGCACACCAAUUUAUAUACAAUACUUUGUGAAGUUCUUCAUUAUUGGAGUUACAGUUUUAGUGGUCGCAGUGCCAGAAGGUCUUCCACUUGCAGUCACGAUCUCACUGGCUUAUUCAGUCAAAAAAAUGAUGAAAGAUAAUAACUUAGUAAGGCAUCUGGAUGCUUGUGAAACCAUGGGAAAUGCUACAGCUAUUUGUUCAGAUAAAACAGGAACUUUGACAAUGAACAGAAUGACAGUCGUUCAAGCUUACAUAAAUGAAAAACAUUAUAAAAAGGUUCCUGAACCAGAAGCUAUUCCACCAAAUAUUUUGUCCUAUCUUGUAACAGGAAUUUCUGUGAAUUGUGCUUAUACAUCAAAAAUAUUGCCACCAGAGAAAGAGGGUGGAUUACCUCGUCACGUUGGUAAUAAAACUGAAUGUGCCUUGUUGGGACUUCUUUUGGAUUUAAAACGGGAUUAUCAGGAUGUUAGAAAUGAAAUACCAGAAGAAGCACUGUACAAAGUCUACACCUUCAAUUCUGUUAGGAAGUCCAUGAGUACUGUCCUGAAAAAUUCAGAUGGAAGUUAUCGAAUAUUCAGCAAGGGUGCAUCUGAGAUAAUUCUGAAAAAGUGUUUCAAAAUCUUGAGUGCUAAUGGUGAGGCAAAAGUAUUCAGACCAAGGGACCGUGAUGAUAUUGUAAAAACUGUGAUUGAACCGAUGGCAUCAGAAGGCUUGAGAACCAUAUGUCUUGCAUUCAGAGAUUUUCCAGCAGGAGAACCAGAACCAGAGUGGGAUAAUGAAAAUGAUAUUGUCACCGGCCUUACAUGCAUUGCUGUUGUGGGGAUUGAAGAUCCUGUGAGACCUGAGGUGCCAGAUGCAAUUAAAAAGUGUCAGAGGGCUGGAAUUACUGUGCGGAUGGUCACUGGUGAUAAUAUUAAUACUGCUCGGGCCAUUGCUACCAAAUGUGGUAUUUUACAUCCUGGGGAAGAUUUUCUGUGCCUAGAAGGUAAAGAUUUUAACAGAAGAAUACGAAAUGAAAAAGGAGAGAUUGAGCAAGAGAGGAUAGACAAGAUUUGGCCAAAACUUCGAGUACUUGCAAGAUCAUCUCCUACUGAUAAGCAUACACUGGUUAAAGGUAUAAUUGACAGCACUGUCUCAGACCAACGCCAGGUUGUAGCUGUAACUGGUGAUGGUACAAAUGAUGGCCCAGCACUAAAGAAAGCAGAUGUUGGAUUUGCAAUGGGUAUUGCUGGAACUGAUGUAGCUAAAGAAGCAUCCGAUAUUAUUCUCACAGAUGACAACUUUACAAGCAUUGUUAAAGCAGUUAUGUGGGGACGAAAUGUCUAUGACAGCAUCUCAAAAUUCCUUCAGUUCCAACUUACUGUUAAUGUAGUAGCAGUGAUUGUUGCUUUUACGGGCGCCUGCAUUACUCAAGACUCACCGCUUAAGGCUGUGCAGAUGCUGUGGGUAAACCUCAUAAUGGAUACACUCGCUUCCCUGGCUCUGGCAACGGAACCACCCACUGAGUCUCUCUUGCUUCGGAAACCUUAUGGUAGAAAUAAGCCUCUCAUCUCACGUACAAUGAUGAAGAAUAUUUUGGGUCAUGCAUUCUAUCAACUUGUAGUAGUCUUUACACUCUUAUUUGCUGGAGAAAAGUUUUUUGACAUUGAUAGUGGAAGAAAUGCUCCUUUGCAUGCUCCUCCUUCAGAACAUUAUACUAUUGUUUUUAAUACCUUUGUGCUGAUGCAACUUUUCAACGAAAUAAAUGCCCGGAAAAUUCAUGGUGAAAGAAAUGUAUUCGAAGGAAUCUUUAACAAUGCCAUCUUCUGCACAAUUGUUUUAGGCACUUUUGUGGUACAGAUAAUAAUUGUGCAGUUUGGUGGAAAACCUUUCAGUUGUUCAGAACUUUCAAUAGAACAGUGGCUAUGGUCAAUAUUCCUAGGAAUGGGAACAUUACUCUGGGGCCAGCUUAUUUCAACAAUUCCAACUAGCCGUUUAAAAUUCCUCAAAGAAGCUGGUCAUGGAACACAAAAGGAAGAAAUACCUGAGGAGGAAUUAGCAGAGGAUGUUGAAGAGAUUGAUCACGCUGAAAGGGAGUUGCGGCGUGGCCAAAUCUUGUGGUUUAGAGGUCUGAACAGAAUCCAAACACAGAUGGAUGUAGUGAAUGCUUUCCAGAGUGGAAGUUCCAUUCAGGGGGCUCUAAGGCGGCAACCCUCCAUCGCCAGCCAGCAUCAUGAUAUUCGAGUGGUGAAUGCAUUUCGUAGUUCUUUAUAUGAAGGGUUAGAAAAACCGGAAUCAAGAAGUUCGAUUCACAACUUUAUGACACAUCCUGAGUUUAGGAUAGAAGAUUCAGAGCCUCAUAUCCCCCUUAUUGAUGACACUGAUGCCGAAGAUGAUGCUCCUACAAAACGUAACUCCAGUCCUCCACCCUCUCCCAACAAAAAUAACAAUGCUGUUGACAGUGGAAUUCACCUUACAAUAGAAAUGAACAAGUCUGCUACCUCUUCAUCCCCAGGAAGCCCACUACAUAGUUUGGAAACAUCACUCUGAUUGUAAGCUGAAUGUUAACACACUAGCUGCAUUGUAAAGAAACAAAUUGAAACUGGGUCUUUUCACAUAUUGUGAUGGACAAGCUAGUAUUCUUGUCUUUGGACUUCAACAGAAGACACACUUGUACGAAUGUAGAUUUAUUUUUUUAAAAAAAAAAAAGCAAAGCUUUCUGCCAGACUGAGGGUGCUUUUUGGGGGGUGGGAGAAAUGAACUGACAGAUAAACAGUAACUCAGCGUAAGUGACCUGUGGAUCAUCAGUAGUACCCAAGCAUGGUCCUGAACAGUGUAUUAGCAGAGCUUUAGUUUAUCUCAGUCCUGGAUGGGAGAGAGAGGGAGGAGUAAAACUGGGCAAGACAAAGAGCCCUGGAUCGUUGAAUUGAUAGUUUAAUUUCUGCUGUUGGCUGUUAAUAAUUUGGAUUAUUUAUGUUUAUAAAUGAUACAGAUCUGUUUACAAGGUUUGUAGAUACUUUUUUUGUUCCUGUUCAUAGAUGGGAAGCUUCCUUAUAACUGAUGCAGAGAAAAAUUAGUCCUUCAAAUACUGCUGUAUUUUCAGGAAAAAAAAAAAAAGGGGUGUUUCUAUUGAAACUGUACUAAAUUUUUGCCUACAAUUUACCUUGUUAAAUAUUGUAGAUAAAUUGCUAAUACUAAUAGCCAAAUAGAUAACACUAAUGCUUUGUUUAAAAAAACGAAAAAAACAAAACAAAACAAAAAAACAUGAGCAGUGGUGUUCUAAUGAAGUUAUGACAUCUGUCCUAAUUAGUUUCUUAAAUACAUUUACUACUUAAUGGUUUUGAAGCAACUGUUUAAUUUUUAAAAUUUUUGAAAACUUGCUAAUAACCUUUUGUUCAGAAUUUAGUAGAUUGUUUAAUGCAGGACAUCAACUACAUAAUGAAAGAUGCUUGAAAUGCUUUUGUUAUUUCAGGCAAAUCAAAUUAAAUCAGACUAUCAAACUACAAGAGAACCUUAGUCUUUUUUGUUUUUGUCUAAACAUGUUAGUUUAGUGAUGUCUUGGUGAACUGUGAGUGAACUGUAUUGAUUUUUCUAAUCUUUAGAGACCUUCACACAGCAUGAGGGCUGUUGGCAUUUUGAAAAAGGUUAAUAAGUAGAAGCAUACAUGUUUUCCUUUUGUUUUUGAAACUUGUUUGUAAACAUAAAUAAAUAUGCCCUUUUAUUAAAUAAAUUCAUGGCAAUGUUUUUUUAAAAGACAUUUCAGCUUCUUUACUCAGUUCUGCAUAUACAGUGCAUCAGUCUGUUCUCUUUGACCACAAUUGGAAUACAUUUCAAGAUGGUAACAGCCCCAUGAAGUACCGCUUUAAUUCCUUGCUGGUAAUCUAAUAGAAUCAGAUUAAGAAAAUUAACACAAUUUUACCAUUUGACAUACUCUUCAUUGAAUUUAGUUUGUCUAAAAUAGUCUCACAGGUAAAAAACAUAACAACAAUGACCACCAUUGUCUUUGAUACAUUUAUUUUAAUUCUUAAGUGGCCAAAUAACAGAUUAGGUAAAAUGAGAUUACAUGAAAAGGUUCUAAAAUGAUAUAUUUAGAUGCAAUAAUUAACCAUAUGCUAGAAUGCCCACCUCUAAGCCAAUUGGAUUCUUUAGCUCUCUUUUUCUUUCCUUCAUCUACCUUCUUCUCUUUUUUGCCUCUGUCUUUACCCUUUAGAAACUGGCAUGUGUUAGGGCCCAGAUUUCACCAGAUACACAAUCCUCAGGCUGACAUAAAGUUUACGAGGACUGCUACUAUAACUGAGAGUGCUGACCAAGCAAAGAAACAUUUAGUUGAUGGUGCUUGAUAUUUUUGGUGGGUGGGGGAAAUCUUUUUCUCACCAUCAAAUCUUUGCAGUAAUCCUCUGCAGGUCUUAGAAACACAUUGGCUCUGUCAGCAUUUGUAAUUGUACAUUUAUUCAUCAGGUAUUUAUAGUGAAUCAUACUGUAAAAAAGAGGUAGCAUGAUAUGCUGGAAAGCAUAUUAGACUAGGAGUCAAGACCUGGUUUCUAGUCUUGGUUUUGCCAUUAAUGUGCUGCAUGAUCUUGGGAAAAUCAUUUACCCUAAAUAAGGGUGGUGGACUAUCUUGAAGAACCCUUUCAACUCUAAAAAUUGACCCUAUCAACUGGAGAGCCCACAAGGCAUAGGGAAUAGAGAAAAGGGAAAUGUUUUCAGUUUUCUUUUUUAUUUUGGUUAUGCUUAAAUAUGAAUGUAAUUACCAAAAGAUUUAGAAGUGCAUGUGCUUUGGAGGAUUUGUAUUGAGCUUUUACAGUAUUCAUUUUUCAACUCAAGGCAAUGGCUUUCUACACCAACUCUAAUCCAUAAACGGGUCUUAUGACAUCUAUGAAGUAGUAGCAAGACAUGCUUAGUGUGUAUUUCUCUCUUUGAGACACUGUAAUUUCUACCAGAAAUUUCCAGAGCAUUAUGUAGGUAGAAAAAAAUGCAAGCAAGCUGUUAAAGAUCUUGGAUCCCAUUAUAUAGUAUGUAUAGCUGAAAUCUGUAAUUCAAUCACUUUUUCUCUUUUAUCCUCUAACCAAAAAAUUGUUUAAUUUUGCAUCCCAAAUGUUUUUAAUCUUUGUAUAUUUUUUAAAAAUCCUUUUCUCCUCAUCAUUGCCUUUUUUGUGGUUGUAAAUAGACUUACUUGCACUUUGAAGAUGAGUUACUCCUUGUCAUCUUACAAAUAUGUGAUAUGGUAAUUUUCAUAACAGAUGUCAGUUUUGAACCAAGAAUUGGUGAUUUGUUUAUAAGAAAAAAACUGGCUUCAUUUCUGUGAAAUUGCUCUUUGAAAAUUUCUUUUUACACGUGUAAGCCAACUGAGAUACCGUGAUGGUGUUGAUUUCUUUCAAUGAUGCUUACCAUCUAUUUUAGCCACUGAGCCUUUUAUUAUUUGUCUAUUUGUAAAGUUUAUUUGUCUUAACUCAUUUAAUAAAUAUACUGUUUAUCUGUUUCUGAA